AGAAGUUAGGAGGUCUGCGUCUGGGUCUCGGCUCACCCUGGGGGGCCGCGGCCAUGGGGCUUAGUUCCUAGCCUAGGAAGGGAAACUGAGACUCUGGGAGGGGCAGGAACGCCCCCAAGGUCACUUGGAAAGUCGGGCAGGAUGUGCUGUUAGGGGGAAGACCCGGGCAGGGUUUUUGUUCCCCGCUGACGACGCCUCCUUUGUGUGUUCGCGCCGCCGCCCCGCCAUCGUGGGGCCUGCGAGUUUGCCGGGGUGCGUGGGCCGCGUGGCGGGGCCUUUUGUAGGUCGGGAGGAUCUGAGUACGGGUGCGGGCCUGACCGUGGGGGCGCCGAGGUCGCAGUCUAAAACUUAGUAGGGCCUCGAUUUCCGGGCGCGCUUCCGGGCCCCGGCUGGUGGUUGGUGGAACGUGCGACUGUGAGGCUUGCGGCCCAGCCCUGCACCGCUCGGGCCCUUCACCGCUCUGGCGCGCCUAUAGACAGGUGUAUGAAGAUUCUCACGACCCGAAACAGAGUUGCUAGUAAACACCGCUUUUCCGCCUUUGAUCCAUCGAGGGAAGAGGGAAAAGGAUAGAGCUUGGGCAAGCCGUUUUGGUGGAAUCUCACUCUGUCACCCAGGAUGCAGUGCACUGGCGUGUUCUCGGUCUCACUGUAACCUCUGCCAUCUGGGCUCAAGUGAUUCUCCUGCCUCAGCCUCCGGAGUAGCUGGGAUUACAGGACUUGAAAAUACUGGAAAUCUGUCCGGAUCCAAAUUAUUUUGCAAGCCAGAUGAGUAACCAGAGGGCAUGAAAGGUUGAGAACAUUUGACUUCCCUGCAAACCUUGGUAUAGAUCACUUCCUUUUCUGUAGGAAAGGAAAGGCACCAAAGAGCACAAUGAGUACAAGAAAGCGUCGUGGUGGAGCAAUAAAUUCUAGACAAGCUCAGAAGCGAACUCGGGAAGCAACCUCCACCCCCGAGAUCUCCUUGGAAGCAGAACCCAUAGAACUCGUGGAAACUGCUGGAGAUGAAAUUGUGGACCUCACUUGUGAAUCUUUAGAGCCUGUGGUGGUUGAUCUGACUCACAAUGACUCUGUUGUGAUUGUUGACGAAAGAAGAAGACCAAGGAGGAAUGCUAGGAGGCUGCCCCAGGACCAUGCUGACAGCUGUGUGGUGAGCAGUGACGAUGAGGAGUUGUCCAGGGACAGAGACGUAUAUGUGACUACCCAUACUCCCAGAAACGCCAGGGAUGAGGGCGCUACAGGCCUCAGGCCCUCAGGUACUGUCAGUUGUCCCAUCUGCAUGGACGGAUACUCAGAGAUCGUGCAGAAUGGACGUCUCAUCGUUUCCACAGAAUGCGGCCAUGUCUUCUGUAGCCAGUGCCUCCGUGAUUCCCUGAAGAAUGCUAAUACUUGCCCAACUUGUAGGAAAAAGAUCAACCACAAACGGUACCACCCCAUUUAUAUAUGAAGUAUUCAGAGCCCCCCAGGAGAGACGGAUGGACAGACAGACAGCCAGGUUCUCCAGUGGUAUCUGCCUCCAUUUUCCUGAGAUCAAAAAGACUGUUUCGAAACCAACAUCUGAUAUGUAAACUGCUCUUUUGUUUCCAACCCCUUCCUUUUGUUAUCUCCAGUUUGAUGCUAUGGCGCUGGACCCAGGGCCCUCCCAGGCCAUCUCUGUUCCUCUGGGGUGGUCCAGUUCUAGAGUGGGAGAAAGGGAGUCAGGCGCAUUGGGAAUCGUGGUUCCAGUCUGGUUGCAGAAUCUGCACAUUUGCCAAGAAAUUUUCCCUGUUUGGAAAGUUUGCCCCAGCUUUCCCGGGCACACCACCUUUUGUCCCAAGUGUCUGCCGGUCGACCAAUCUGCCUGCCACACAUUGACCAAGCCAGACCCGGUUCACCCAGCUCGAGGAUCCCAGGUUGAAGAGUGGCCCCUUGAGGCCCUGGAAAGACCAAUCACUGGACUUCUUCCCUUGAGAGUCAGAGGUCACCCGUGAUUCUGCCUGCACCUUAUCAUUGAUCUGCAGUGAUUUCUGCAAAUCAAGAGAAACUCUGCAGGGCACUCCCCUGUUUCCUAAGAACGAAAAAGUGCAAUAAAGGCCAUUCGUUACCUACUUUUCAGCAGCCCACAAGAUGUAGCACUAUUAGUGUCCCCCUCAGAGGCUUAAUGUUGCCUGUGGAGCAGUGCCCAUCCCAGCCCGUUUCUGCCCACCAGUUGUUCUCAGGAACCUUACCCAUGCUCCAGCGUCCUUCACCUGGCACAGGACAUGCAAGAUAAAUAGGGCAGGCACGUGUUUGGGUGUCCUCUCUUUUCUGAUAAAAUCCAUCCCGUGUUUGCCACACGCCCUCCAGUCCUCAGUUCCCACUGCCUAACGUCUGCCCCCGUGUAGAUACUGAGAGGUGGUGGCAGUAAUUGUGGCCUUAUCAGCCGCUCAGUUCCAGGCUUUUGCCCAGGUCACUGUUGCCCCAUGUUCGGAGAACCUGGCCCACCUGUCUUGGCUUUCUCAUCCUUCCCAACCCAGUGCCGUUUAUUUCAGAAGCUUCCUGGCCACUGGGCUUGGAUGCUUCGGGCUUCUGACUGCUCCAUAGGUUUUGACUGGUGAAACAGGGGCCCAGAUGACAACCUCUCCUUCGCUCCACAGGUACGCGGGAGCCUCAGGUUCUCUCAGGGGCAGCAAAGUGGCCCAAGCUGCCCCUGACAGCACAGGGCCUGGGGGGUGGCUAACGAGAGAGGCCUUACAGUGCCGGCAUGCCUCCUCUUCCACUGUCGUCCUUCCUCAGAGGGCCUCACGCCAAACAAACGGCCUUUUCGUGUGAAACAUCUUCAGGGCGGGAAAGGGGCCACUUCUGGCUUUGUUAGCAAUAACUGACCUUCAGUUUACCCUUCUGAAGGAGCAGGGACUCAGCACAGAAUUCACUUUAGACGGGGCUGAAGGAGUGUCCCUCCUCUAUGUGAAAAGAAAAUUGUUUUAUUCUUCAUUCUGACUUUUUAACUGUUUGGCUCACUUCCAGUUAGUUUGAAUGAAAAUAAUAAUUUUCUACUUGGAGUUGAAGAGGGCAGAAUCCGCAGCUCUCAUCAUUGUGAUGUGUAGCAUGUCUGCCCUCUGACUGGACAUCAUUGCCAUUAACUUUCUUCUGGGCAUCACGGCAAUGUCACGAUGCCCAGACUUGGAGCAAGGCAACCUUGGAGUCAGUCCACUCAUAAAAUAUGGUAACACCCAUUUUAAAAUUUAAGUUUUGUCCUUAAAGACAACUUCAGUGGUUAAUUAUAAAAGUUGUGUUACUUCGUCCUAAAUUAAAUUGAUAGAAAGAUUUAAAAAUGUGUUUUGUUUCUACUAUUCAGAAACUGCGAACUAGGGAAAGGUUGGUAUGAAGAAAUGUCUUUCCUUUUUUCAAUGUACAUAGUUCAACUCUUUCUUUGUUACAUUUAAACUAUAUCCAUGGAUAUCAGUCUGCUUUGGACUCCUCUGCUAGUGUUACAGAUGGAAAUAAAACCAUUAAUUUGAACCAAA